ACCCCCUCUUUCUGGCGUCCAUCCCCUCCCCAACACCACCUCUGCUGCUGCCUCUGGCUGUGGACCUGCACCUCUUCCCCAUCCCCGCCAGGCCCGGGGAGCGGGGUGAGCCUGGAUGAGAGCCCCCCCAACCUGGGGCUCUCCCAGGCCAUGGCCCGUGUGCUCCCAGGGAGGAGCCCCGGACCCUGAGCAUCUGCUGGAGGCUUGGCAGAGGCCCCGCGGGGACCGUGUCUUCUGAGGACAAAAGGCGGCGGCCAGCAGGCAGACGGAGGGGGGGGGUGGGGGGUGGGGGGGGUAGGGGGACCGGCAGCCAGGCAGGCAGACGGGUAGCAGGGGCCAGCACUGGCCCCCCUCCCAGCUUGGCAGUGGCAUGAAGAUGGGAGUGGGAGUGUAUAGUGGAGGAAGCACCUGCCGGGACCCCCACCUGCCAGCUAGUUGGACACCCCAAGGCUGUGUGCUGCCCACCUGGUGUUCCCCAACACCCCCAGCCCUACCCAGUGCACCCCUCCGGUGCCUGCUUUCCCUGAUGCCUGCGAUUUAGACCAGCCCGGCUGUAUCCACGGCAACAGAAGCAGGAGUGUCACUGGCCGCCAGAUCACUGAGGGUCCCACAAUGUGGCCCGGGCUGUGAUUUACCUGGGUGAGACAGCUUGAGCCCCAUCGUGGAUUCCAAGACAUCCCUGCUGAGAGAGCCAAGAUGGAGUUUCGCUCUUGUUGUCCAGGCUGGAGUGCAAUGGCGCAAUCUCAGCUCACCACAACCUCCACCUCCCGGGUUCAAGUGAUUCUCCUGCCUCAGCCUCCCCAGUAGCUGGGAUUACAGGCAUGUGCCACCACGCCCUGUUAAUUUUGUAUUUUUUUAUUUUUAGUGGAGACGGGGUUUCUCCAUGUUGGUCAGGCUGGUCUCGAACUCCGUGCCUCAGGUGAUCCGCCCACCUCCGCUUCUGAAAGUGCUGGGAUUACAGGCGUGAGCCACUGUGCCCGGCCCCCAAUGUCUUAUACUGGGUAACUAUGGAUUUAGGAGAAGGGGAAACAUCAGAGGCAGGACGUGCAGGAAAAUGACAGGCACAGGCCUUGGAGGUGCAAUGUAGCAGGACAACUCAUGGAGCCCCCCCGGGCCCAUCGAGUACCGGACUGGCUGACCCCCUAGGGUUGGCAGUAGCCCCUGACCCUCAGUAUGGCCAACACUACCGGAGAGCCUGAGGAGGUGAGCGGCGCUCUGUCCCCACCGUCCGCAUCAGCUUAUGUGAAGCUGGUACUGCUGGGACUGAUUAUGUGCGUGAGCCUGGCGGGUAACGCCAUCUUGUCCCUGCUGGUGCUCAAGGAGCGUGCCCUGCACAAGGCUCCUUACUACUUCCUGCUGGACCUGUGCCUGGCCGAUGGCAUACGCUCUGCCGUCUGCUUCCCCUUUGUGCUGGCUUCUGUGCGCCACGGCUCUUCAUGGACCUUCAGUGCACUCAGCUGCAAGAUUGUGGCCUUUAUGGCCGUGCUCUUUUGCUUCCAUGCGGCCUUCAUGCUGUUCUGCAUCAGCGUCACCCGCUACAUGGCCAUCGCCCACCACCGCUUCUACGCCAAGCGCAUGACACUCUGGACAUGCGCGGCUGUCAUCUGCAUGGCCUGGACCCUGUCUGUGGCCAUGGCCUUCCCACCUGUCUUUGACGUGGGCACCUACAAGUUUAUUCGGGAGGAGGACCAGUGCAUCUUUGAGCAUCGCUACUUCAAGGCCAAUGACACGCUGGGCUUCAUGCUUAUGUUGGCUGUGCUCAUGGCAGCUACCCAUGCUGUCUACGGCAAGCUGCUCCUCUUCGAGUAUCGUCACCGCAAGAUGAAGCCAGUGCAGAUGGUGCCAGCCAUCAGCCAGAACUGGACAUUCCAUGGUCCCGGGGCCACCGGCCAGGCUGCUGCCAACUGGAUCGCCGGCUUUGGCCGUGGGCCCAUGCCACCAACCCUGCUGGGUAUCCGGCAGAAUGGGCAUGCAGCCAGCCGGCGGCUACUGGGCAUGGACGAGGUCAAGGGUGAAAAGCAGCUGGGCCGCAUGUUCUACGCGAUCACACUGCUCUUUCUGCUCCUCUGGUCACCCUACAUCGUGGCCUGCUACUGGCGAGUGUUUGUGAAAGCCUGUGCUGUGCCCCACCGCUACCUGGCCACUGCUGUUUGGAUGAGCUUCGCCCAGGCUGCCGUCAACCCAAUUGUCUGCUUCCUGCUCAACAAGGACCUCAAGAAGUGCCUGAGGACUCACGCCCCCUGCUGGGGCACAGGAGGUGCCCCGGCUCCCAGAGAACCCUACUGUGUCAUGUGAAGCAGGCUGGUAGGCAGACAGGCAGAGAGAAGGUCAUGGCCACCGUGAUGGGGCCAACAGCAAGGGAGGGGUAGGGGCCCAUACAGGAGUCCUCCUUUCUGAGCUCCAGCCCCAGCCCCUCGAACCACCUGUAAUCUAGGCACCUUUGCCAACACCUCCCAAGGAUGGAGGACUGGGCGAGGGACUGGGAAAGAGGCAUAUUUAGUUUUGUGGGGCCUGUCUCCGCUGCCUCCUUCUCCACUUCUACAAUCUCAUUCUCUCUCUCUCUCUCUCUGUCUCUCUCUCUCUCUCUCUCUCUCUCUCAGAAGUGACAAUUCAGAAAAAGAAAAGAACACUGAGAAUGCAGGUUUUUCUACUAACAGCUGAGGAGACAGGCUUUCUUACUUUAAUGUCUCUCCUUCUGACACUGUCCAGAAGGGGGAAUUUGUCCUGUAAAAUAGACUUCCAGAGCUCUUUUGCCCCCUCUGCUCCCAUGCACCCUCCCCUUCCAAGUCCUUUAGCAAGGCCUGGAUGUUUAGGGAGAAAGUGGUCCAAGGCUGCUGACAAGAGGGACCAAAGGGGGUGCUGGGUUCCCAGGGAGCAGGGAUGUUUAAUUACUAUGUCAUGUGCAAUGUUGUUUUAGGCCAACCCUUGCCCCAAGCCCAGUCUCUUCUCCCUCCCCACCAUGUCCAGACCUCCCAAAUGGUUCUUGUGCAUCUGUUGGAGAAGUCAAGGGAGUAGGGAGAAGGGCCCCAAGGAUGGGCCCAGGUUAGGUGAAGAGUAAGAUGUGAGCUGAACUCCUCGAACUGAAGAGACCCACACUUGGUCACAUUCUCUCACGCUGCCUUCAGGAUCCCCAGCCCCCAACUCUUCUUCCUGAGGAUGGAAAUCCACUCCAGCCCCACUAGGACUGAUGUGGGUGCCAUACAGGCAGGAGCAGCCCACCAGGAAAGUGUAAGGAGGGAGCUGAACUCCCCAGAGUAGCUGGACCACAGAGACUUGGGUCAGAGCUGAUUUCAACCCCAGAAUUGUCUCUCGGGUUCACCCUACUCUUCUGAAGAUGAAAAUUUGUUUGGGGCCUUGGUAACCGAUAGCGGUACAAACUCCAAGGCACUGUGGACUUGAGUCCAUUCCUAUCUGACCUCUUUUUGUCCCCCUCAAGCCUCAGGGGCCUCAAGCCCCUCCUUAGUAGCCCUUGGCUGACUGGGCCCUGAGCCCCAAGCAUCCUUCUUUCCCAACAACCCUCCUUCCCCAUCCUUCCCCCACCCUUACCUACACCCAAAGUGGAGCACACUGCAGUCAGAUUCUCCAGGAGGGAGAUCCAAGCCUCCUCCCAGGGGUGGAGUCCACUCUGGGCUUACUUUGAGGCCUGUUCUGUGGAUUGGUGAGCCAAGCUGGCACUCCUUGCCCUGGUCUUACCCAGGCUCUCUGUCCCCCUCUCACUUCCUGUGGGGCCGGAAUCUGUAUUUAUCCAUCCCCCUUUCCCUUCUUUAUAGAAGUCCCUGUCCUAAACUCCCUCCCUAGCCCAAGAGAGCCCCAGAACUGGGGAAGCCUGACCCAUACAGAAUGGGGAGGGCACUCUAGGCAGGAGAGACAUUAAUGAGCCUGGCUGCAGAGUGGCCCUGGAAAGGCAGGCCAGAGUGGCUGAGAGGCUGGGAGUAGGGGAGCCUGUUCUCUCAGCGAUAGUGAUGGGGGUGCCUUUCCGAGGGGGUGGGGUGGGAAGACCAAGGGGGUGGGGGGUAGAUAGGGUACAUUUAGGAGGGUUUUCCUCCAUUUCUUUUUUCUAACUGCCUGGAUUCACCAUUGGAUUUUGUAAAUGGAAAAACUGAAAUGAACAAUGCUAUACUGGAUGUUUUCUCUUUCUGACUGUGUGUGUGUGUGUGCGUGCGUGCGUGCAUGUGCCCUGUCUGACCACAUGUGGAGAGACAUGAUUGAGUGAUAGUGUGUGUCUGUGUGACUUUGUGUGGGGAGGCACUCCUGAAGAAAACUUGCCCGGUGCACACACGUAAAAUGCCUGUAUAUGGGGACAGAUACAGCACGUGCAUGCAUACACACACACACACACACACCACAGUUGAGAGGAGACAAACUAGAGUAUGUGCCCGUGGUAGGAAGUCGAGUGGUCAAGAGAUGGAUCUUGGAAACUACAUAGGUCGGUAGCAAGAGGGUAGACUCCCAUCUCACAAGAUGGGCCUCCCUUGGCCCAGGCCCUGAGCACGGGAGGGCUGGGGCCGCCAGGGAACUUGAAAACCUCAUCUCCUCACAAAGCCUGUAGCCCCAUCUCAACCCCGUCUCAGUCUCCUUCCCAAACUCAAACAAGGUGUUCCUAAAAUUGGACCACCAUGGAGAAUGGGGACUGGGAAUUGAGGAUCAAAUGUGAGGGAAACUGAUGAGGUUAGGAAAUGCCCCCCACAAAGUAAUGGCUUCUGGAGGGACUGCUCAGUCUGGGAUGGGAGCCCUUCCUAGGGGCCACUGUAUGCAGCUGGGACUUUGGUCAGCUUUGACCAAAUUUAGAGGGAGGGAUGUCAUGGGGAAAAAAAACCCAAGCCCAGGAGUCUACCCAGCCAGCCUGCUCCCUAGACAGUUAAUUUACUAUCUGGUUAUUCUCUCAGGUGCACAGAAUUGAGUUGACCAUACUCCUCAGUUCUUGGCACACUAUAUCAUCAUUGGUCCAUGUGAGGCCCUUUUAUUUUUUUUUCUUCAGUUUUGUCCCCUUCAUCACCCAUUCCUGAUCCCAUCCUCCCCGCCCCCUACACAGGCACCCACUCUCGUGUAUUUAACGUACGUCCUUCCAAUCCACCGUUCAUGUGUUUAUUUACAUAUAUGUGUAUCUGUGAAAAAUGUAUGGUAUUGCUGUGUGUUUUAAUUUACAUAAACAGUAUUGUACUAUAAA